GUUCUACGAGGACAACAGCACUUGGGAUGUGCACCAACAGUUCUUAUGGGGGCCCGGCCUCCUCAUCACUCCAGUUCUGGAUGAAGGUGCAGAGAAAGUGAUGGCAUAUGUGCCUGAUGCUGUCUGGUAUGACUACGAGACUGGGAGCCAAGUGAGAUGGAGGAAGCAAAAAGUCGAGAUGGAACUUCCUGGAGACAAAAUUGGACUUCACCUUCGAGGAGGCUACAUCUUCCCCACACAGCAGCCAAAUACAACCACUCUGGCCAGUCGAAAGAACCCUCUUGGUCUUAUCAUUGCCCUAGAUGAGAACAAAGAAGCAAAAGGAGAACUUUUCUGGGAUAAUGGGGAAACGAAGGAUACUGUGGCCAAUAAAGUGUAUCUUUUAUGUGAGUUUUCUGUCACUCAAAACCGCUUGGAGGUGAAUAUUUCACAAUCAACCUACAAGGACCCCAAUAAUUUAGCAUUUAAUGAGAUUAAAAUUCUUGGGACGGAGGAACCUAGCAAUGUUACAGUGAAACACAAUGGUGUCCCAAGUCAGACUUCUCCUACAGUCACUUAUGAUUCUAACCUGAAGGUUGCCAUUAUCACAGAUAUUGAUCUUCUCCUGGGAGAAGCAUACACAGUGGAAUGGAGCAUAAAGAUAAGGGAUGAAGAAAAAAUAGACUGUUACCCUGAUGAGAAUGGUGCUUCUGCCGAAAACUGCACUGCCCGUGGCUGUAUCUGGGAGGCAUCCAAUUCUUCUGGAGUCCCUUUUUGCUAUUUUGUCAACGACCUAUACUCUGUCAGUGAUGUUCAGUAUAAUUCCCAUGGGGCCACAGCUGACAUCUCCUUAAAGUCUUCCGUUUAUGCCAAUGCCUUCCCCUCCACACCCGUGAACCCCCUUCGCCUGGAUGUCACUUACCAUAAGAAUGAAAUGCUGCAGUUCAAGAUUUAUGAUCCCAACAAGAAUCGGUAUGAAGUUCCAGUCCCUCUGAACAUACCCAGCAUGCCAUCCAGCACCCCUGAGGGUCAACUCUAUGAUGUGCUCAUUAAGAAGAAUCCAUUUGGGAUUGAAAUUCGCCGGAAGAGUACAGGCACUAUAAUUUGGGACUCUCAGCUCCUUGGCUUUACCUUCAGUGACAUGUUUAUCCGCAUCUCCACCCGCCUUCCCUCCAAGUACCUCUAUGGCUUUGGGGAAACUGAGCACAGGUCCUAUAGGAGAGACUUGGAGUGGCACACUUGGGGGAUGUUCUCCCGAGACCAGCCCCCAGGGUACAAGAAGAAUUCCUAUGGUGUCCACCCCUACUACAUGGGGCUGGAGGAGGACGGCAGUGCCCAUGGAGUGCUCCUGCUGAACAGCAAUGCCAUGGAUGUGACGUUCCAGCCCCUGCCUGCCUUGACAUACCGCACCACAGGGGGAGUUCUGGACUUUUAUGUGUUCUUGGGGCCGACUCCAGAGCUUGUCACCCAGCAGUACACUGAGUUGAUUGGCCGGCCUGUGAUGGUACCUUACUGGUCUUUGGGGUUCCAGCUGUGUCGCUAUGGCUACCAGAAUGACUCUGAGAUCGCCAGCUUGUAUGAUGAGAUGGUGGCUGCCCAGAUCCCUUAUGAUGUGCAGUACUCAGACAUCGACUACAUGGAGCGGCAGCUGGACUUCACCCUCAGCCCCAAGUUUGCUGGGUUUCCAGCUCUGAUCAAUCGCAUGAAGGCUGAUGGGAUGCGGGUCAUCCUCAUUCUGGAUCCAGCCAUUUCUGGCAAUGAGACACAGCCUUAUCCUGCCUUCACUCGGGGCGUGGAGGAUGACGUCUUCAUCAAAUACCCAAAUGAUGGAGACAUUGUCUGGGGAAAGGUCUGGCCUGAUUUUCCUGAUGUUGUUGUGAAUGGGUCUCUAGACUGGGACAGCCAAGUGGAGCUAUAUCGAGCUUAUGUGGCCUUCCCAGACUUUUUCCGUAAUUCAACUGCCAAGUGGUGGAAGAGGGAAAUAGAAGAACUAUACAACAAUCCACAGAAUCCAGAGAGGAGCUUGAAGUUUGAUGGCAUGUGGAUUGAUAUGAAUGAACCAUCAAGCUUCGUGAAUGGGGCAGUUUCUCCAGGCUGCAGGGACGCCUCUCUGAACCACCCUCCCUACAUGCCACAUUUGGAGUCCAGGGACAGGGGCCUGAGCAGCAAGACCCUUUGUAUGGAGAGUCAGCAGAUCCUCCCAGACGGCUCCCUGGUGCAGCACUACAACGUGCACAACCUGUAUGGGUGGUCCCAGACCAGACCCACAUACGAAGCCGUGCAGGAGGUGACGGGACAGCGAGGGGUCGUCAUCACCCGCUCCACAUUUCCCUCUUCUGGCCGCUGGGCAGGACAUUGGCUGGGAGACAACACGGCCGCAUGGGAUCAGCUGAAGAAGUCUAUCAUUGGCAUGAUGGAGUUCAGCCUCUUUGGCAUAUCCUAUACGGGAGCAGAUAUCUGUGGGUUCUUUCAAGACGCUGAGUACGAGAUGUGUGUUCGCUGGAUGCAGCUGGGGGCCUUUUACCCCUUCUCAAGAAACCACAAUACCAUUGGGACCAGGAGACAAGACCCUGUGUCCUGGGAUGCUGCUUUUGUGAAUAUUUCCAGAAAUGUCCUGCAGACCAGAUACACCCUGUUGCCAUAUCUGUAUACCUUGAUGCAAAAGGCCCACACGGAGGGCGUCACUGUUGUGCGGCCUCUGCUCCAUGAGUUUGUGUCAGACCAGGUGACAUGGGACAUAGACAGUCAGUUCCUGCUGGGCCCAGCCUUCCUGGUCAGCCCUGUCCUGGAGCGCAAUGCCAGAAAUGUCACUGCAUAUUUCCCUAGAGCCCGUUGGUACGAUUACUACACGGGUGUGGAUAUUAAUGCAAGAGGAGAGUGGAAGACCUUGCCAGCCCCUCUUGACCACAUUAAUCUUCAUGUCCGUGGGGGCUACAUCCUGCCCUGGCAAGAGCCUGCACUGAACACCCACUUAAGUCGAAAGAACCCUCUUGGUCUUAUUAUUGCCCUAGAUGAAAACAAAGAAGCAAAAGGAGAACUUUUCUGGGAUGAUGGGCAAACAAAGGAUACUGUGGCCAAGAAAGUAUAUCUUUUAUGUGAGUUUUCUGUCACUCAAAACCACUUGGAGGUGACUAUUUCACAAUCAACCUACAAGGACCCCAAUAAUUUAGCAUUCAAUGAGAUUAAAAUUCUUGGGAUGGAGGAACCUAGCAAUGUUACGGUGAAACACAAUGGUGUCCCAAGUCAGACUUCUCCUACAGUCACUUAUGAUUCUAACCUGAAGGUCGCCAUUAUCACAGACAUCAAUCUUUUCCUGGGAGAAGCAUACACAGUGGAGUGGAGCAUAAAGAUAAGGGAUGAAGAAAAAAUAGACUGUUACCCUGAUGAGAAUGGUGAUUCUGCAGAAAACUGCACUGCCCGUGGCUGUAUCUGGGAGGCAUCCAAUUCUUCUGGAGUCCCUUUUUGCUAUUUUGUCAACGACCUAUACUCUGUCAGUGAUGUUCAGUAUAACUCCCAUGGGGCCACAGCUGACAUCUCCUUAAAGUCUUCUGUUCAUGCCAAUGCCUUCCCUUCCACACCCGUGAACCCCCUUCGCCUGGAUGUCACUUACCAUAAGAAUGAAAUGCUACAGUUCAAGAUUUAUGAUCCCAACAACAAUCGGUAUGAAGUUCCAGUCCCUCUGAACAUACCCAGCGUGCCAUCCAGCACCCCUGAGGGUCAACUCUAUGAUGUCCUCAUUAAGAAGAAUCCAUUUGGGAUUGAAAUUCGCCGGAAGAGUACAGGCACUAUAAUUUGGGACUCUCAGCUCCUUGGCUUCACCUUCAAUGACAUGUUUAUCCGCAUCUCCACCCGCCUUCCCUCCAAGUACCUCUAUGGCUUUGGGGAGACUGAGCACACGUCCUACAGGAGAGACUUGGAGUGGCACACUUGGGGGAUGUUCUCCCGAGACCAGCCCCCAGGGUACAAGAAGAAUUCCUAUGGUGUCCACCCCUACUACAUGGGGCUAGAGGAGGAUGGCAGUGCCCAUGGAGUGCUCCUGCUGAACAGCAAUGCCAUGGAUGUGACGUUCCAGCCCCUGCCUGCCUUGACAUACCGUACCACAGGGGGAGUUCUGGACUUUUAUGUGUUCUUGGGGCCAACUCCAGAGCUUGUCACCCAGCAGUACACUGAGUUGAUUGGCCGGCCUGUGAUGGUACCUUACUGGUCUUUGGGGUUCCAGCUGUGUCGCUAUGGCUACCAGAACGACUCUGAGAUCUCCAGCUUGUAUGAUGAGAUGGUGGCUGCCCAGAUCCCUUAUGACGUGCAGUACUCAGACAUCGACUACAUGGAGCGGCAGCUGGACUUCACCCUCAGCCCCAAGUUUGCCGGGUUUCCAGCUCUGAUCAAUCGCAUGAAGGCUGAUGGGAUGCGGGUCAUCCUCAUUCUGGAUCCAGCCAUUUCUGGCAAUGAGACACAGCCCUAUCCUGCCUUCACUCGGGGCGUGGAGGAUGACGUCUUCAUCAAGUACCCAAAUGAUGGAGACAUUGUCUGGGGAAAGGUCUGGCCUGAUUUUCCUGAUGUUGUUGUGAAUGGGUCUCUAGACUGGGACAGUCAAGUGGAGCUAUAUCGAGCUUAUGUGGCCUUCCCAGACUUUUUCCGUAAUUCAACUGCCAAGUGGUGGAAGAGGGAAAUAGAAGAACUAUACAACAAUCCACAGAAUCCAGAGAGGAGCUUGAAGUUUGAUGGCAUGUGGAUUGAUAUGAAUGAACCAUCAAGCUUCGUGAAUGGGGCAGUUUCUCCAGGCUGCAGGGAUGCCUCUCUGAACCACCCUCCCUACAUGCCGUAUUUGGAGUCCAGGGACAGGGGCCUGAGCAGCAAGACCCUGUGCAUGGAGAGUCAGCAGAUCCUCCCAGACGGCUCCCCGGUGCAGCACUACAAUGUGCACAACCUGUACGGGUGGUCCCAGACCAGACCCACAUACGAAGCCGUGCAGGAGGUGACAGGACAGCGAGGGGUCGUCAUCACCCGCUCCACAUUUCCCUCUUCUGGCCGCUGGGCAGGACAUUGGCUGGGAGACAACACAGCCGCGUGGGAUCAGCUGAAGAAGUCUAUCAUUGGCAUGAUGGAGUUCAGCCUCUUCGGCAUAUCCUAUACGGGAGCAGAUAUCUGUGGGUUCUUUCAAGAUGCUGAAUAUGAGAUGUGUGUUCGCUGGAUGCAGCUGGGGGCCUUUUACCCCUUCUCAAGAAACCACAACACCAUUGGGACCAGGAGACAAGACCCUGUGUCCUGGGAUGUUGCUUUUGUGAAUAUUUCCAGAACUGUCCUGCAGACCAGAUACACCCUGUUGCCAUAUCUGUAUACCUUGAUGCAUAAGGCCCACACGGAGGGCGUCACUGUUGUGCGGCCUCUGCUCCAUGAGUUUGUGUCAGACCAGGUGACAUGGGACAUAGACAGUCAGUUCCUGCUGGGCCCAGCCUUCCUGGUCAGCCCUGUCCUGGAGCGUAAUGCCAGAAAUGUCACUGCAUAUUUCCCUAGAGCCCGCUGGUAUGAUUACUACACGGGUGUGGAUAUUAAUGCAAGAGGAGAGUGGAAGACCUUGCCAGCCCCUCUUGACCACAUUAAUCUUCAUGUCCGUGGGGGCUACAUCCUGCCCUGGCAAGAGCCUGCACUGAACACCCACUUAAGCCGCCAGAAAUUCAUGGGCUUCAAAAUUGCCUUGGAUGAUGAAGGAACUGCUGGGGGCUGGCUCUUCUGGGAUGAUGGGCAAAGCAUUGAUACCUAUGGGAAAGGACUCUAUUACUUGGCCAGCUUUUCUGCCAGCCAGAAUACGAUGCAAAGCCAUAUAAUUUUCAACAAUUACAUCACUGGUACAAAUCCUUUGAAACUGGGCUACAUUGAAAUCUGGGGAGUGGGCAGUGUCCCCGUUACCAGUGUCAGCAUCUCUGUGAGUGGCAUGGUCAUAACACCCUCCUUCAACAAUGACCCCACGACACAGGUAUUAAGCAUCGAUGUGACUGACAGAAACAUCAGCCUACAUAAUUUUACUUCAUUGACGUGGAUAAGCACUCUGUGAAUUUUUACAGCAAGAUUCUAACUAACUAUGAAUGACUUUGAAACUACUUAUACUUCAUACUCAUAAAAAUUAUUGUGUGUUGCUAAUUUGUUCAUACCCACUAUUGGUGAAAUAUUUCUGUUAAUUUUGUUAUAUGUUUUUUGUGUGAACCCUAAAGGUUAAACCUUAGCCCUGUGGGAUAGGCAGUUAGGGAGGUGUGGAAAAUCUAUGCAUUACCUUAAUGUCUCUGUGUGGUUAGUAUGGUAGUGACUGUUCAUCAUAUGACAUUUACUGAAGAUGAACUGGGUCCAUGAUGAAGUGUGUGUAUGUCCACGUUUGUAAUCAUAGAAUGGACCCCAUUCUUUUGUUAAAUACACAAGAGAAAGCUUUCUGUGACAGUUCCAGGUCUUGAAGCUAAUCAGCAUCUCAAGAAAGUAUCCAGAAAGAACAUCUGCUAGUUGGUUAUAGGCGGUGGGAGGAAUAAUAUACCUAAUUGGUUAUAGGUGGGGGGAGCAUGAUAAGCAAAGAAAAGGCAAACACAAGGAAAGAUCAGAUGAAACAGAAGAUGAUAGUAAAAGUGAUCCUAAGUAAGAACAUAAUGUAAAAUUGUCAGCAGCCUCAUGGGGAGGAAAAAGGAAGAGUCAACUCACUUGAAGAAGAGGGUCUUGAGAAAUCCUUAGCAUAAAGGGCUACUGGUGAGAUUGAGAUCUGAGCAGGCAAAGCUCAAAAGAGAGUUUGGAGGUUAAAAAUAAUUUAUUUUUGCAGUAGUGUGCUUUGAAAUGUGUAAAUCUUAUUUCUAAUGUAUACAACCACAUUUCACAUAAAAAUAUGCAAUUUAUAUGCCAGAUAAAAAUAAAACAAGUGAAUUUGCAAGUGA